AAGUGACGCGAGGCUCUGCGGAGACCAGGAGUCAGACUGUAGGACGACCUCGGGUCCCACGUGUCCCCGGUACUCGCCGGCCGGAGCCCCCGGCUUCCCGGGGCCGGGGGACCUUAGCGGCACCCACACACAGCCUACUUUCCAAGCGGAGCCAUGUCUGGUAACGGCAAUGCGGCUGCAACGGCGGUGAGUGCUGAGCCGGUGACCAGCACACUUUGGGCUUCUGGACGAGCCGUGCAGCGAUUGGCCCCAGGUUGCCAUCCUCAGUCGUCUAUUGG